GGAGCUAAAGUGGUCGUGAUUCAUGCUGUCGCGGGAACCCCGAAGGUGGGGCCCCACGUAACAAGAAGAUGACCCGAAGUUGCUCCGCAGUGGGCUGCAGCACCCGUGACACCGUGCUCAGCCGGGAGCGCGGCCUCUCCUUCCACCAGUGCGUAUGGGAGCAGCCUCGAAGCCUUCGAACUCCCUGCGGGGCCCGGCGGGCCGUGGCGUGGCGUGGGGCGGGGCCGGGCCGCACUGUGGGUCGCGCCGCGUGUGUGACGCGACGUGACGUGCGCAGCGUCGGGGCGUGGGAGCGGAAUUGGGGCACUGUGAGAAUUGAGAUUCUCUCUCUUCCCGCCCAGUGUUUACCUCUGAAUAGCCGGUUCUCGCACCGCCUACCGCUUUAAGGAGAGUUACGCGAAAGGAGUCCUCCAUUAAUUGGAUGGUCUUAUUAUUUGAAGUGAGGAGGCCGAAAGGGAAGGCAGUUUAGGACAACGGUUGAAGUGUGUGUGUGGCGUCUUCCUGAGCACGAGUACAGAUCAGUUUUCUCCUGUACUGCCUGACAUUGCAAGUUCUUAAGUGCUGUUAGCCGAGCUGUGCAAGGCCGGUCCGAUUCUGGCUGGAUUUGAUCAUGGCAGGGAAGUUUCAUUUGGCUCGACAGUGGGGAAGAAUUUCAGAUCAGUCUUAUCUGAACUCAUAUCCAUGGUUCAGACUGGUAUAGGUCAUUCAGUAUUCAGGGUACACUAGCAAGUAGAAAAGUGGGUAAAAUAGAUCCUCACAGACAAAAGGAGCAGAUUUAUGGAAAGAUCAAAAAGAACUUUAUGGUUGGAAAGGGGGGGUAGGAAGAGGGUAGUUAGGAAUGGCAUGGGAAAAUGUAAAGGAUAGAAAGUGCAAAUAUAGAGGAGUGGAAAAGUACCUGAGAAACCAUUUUAAAAAUGUAAAUGCCAGGUUAAGGAGUUUAGAGUAUGUAUGGUAGGCUAUGUAUAAAAUUCAUUGAUUUUUUUUUUUUUUUGUUUUCUAUUUUUUAAAUAGGGCUGAUUCCUCCACCUAAAUUGUUAGCAGUGUGAACCAACUCAUUGUGUAUGUGAGACCAUAAUUGAUUUGGGAUUUUUCUUGUGAUAGAGGUAGUUUUAAACUAGGGAGACAUGAAUUCCAAUUUUAAUUGAGUAUUUACUGAUGUCUGUACUUGGCUCUGGGUCUUGGUUUCUUCUUCUGUAAGAGGAAUAAAAACCUGCCUUGUAGAAUUUUGUAAAACUAAAACGUAAGACUUUAUAGCAUAUGUAACGCACAAGGUAAAUGCUUUAAAAAUGGUAUUAUUACCAAAUUAAUUUUUUCCAGAACUCAAAACUAGUUAUGCUAGUUAGAUUACAAUAUUUCCCAACAUUUUCCUUCUUUUUUUUUUUUUUUUUUUUGGAGACGGGGUCUCACUUUGUCGCCCAGGCUGGAGAGCAGUGGCACUAUCACAGCUCAGCGCAGCCUCUAUCUCCCAGGCUCAAGUGAUCCUCCCACCUCAGCCUCAUGGGACUACAGGCACAGACCACCAUCCCGGCUUUUUUUUUUUUUUGGUAGAGAUGAGGUCUCAGUGUGUUGCCCAGGUUGGUCUCCAACUUCUUGGCUGGGAUUACAGGCAUGAGCCACCCUGCCCAGCCCCAGCCUUUUUCAUAGCAUUUUACGCAUAGGAAAUAAUUGUUCAAUACUUUGGGGCAAACCUACAGCACUGUUUGGGGCUGCCUUCAAGUAACUACUCAGGUGUCCCAGCCCACCCCAUGGACUAAGAAUAUCAACAGCUGUACUCACUAGGCAUACCUGUUGGGAAGCUUUGCAUCAGAGGACCACGCUAGUAAUAGAAGUUGUUGGACCAGCCAACUUUUGAGGGUUCCUUGCACGUUUAGAGACUAUACCCAAUCUGUGGAAAAGCUCCCUUGCAAAAUAUGUUCCAUGAGUUAGAAAAGAACUCAGUGAAAAAAGAUAGAUUUGCCCCAACUUUAUUGGAAAAAGAAUUCCCUGUUCAUUUGCCCUUGAUCAAGUAUCAUCAUCUUCUUAGAACAAUAAAAUUAUAAUCCCAGAAAUGGAAUUAGUUGUUCUUAGGAAAGAUCGAACUUUGGAUAGUACUUUACAGUUUACAAAGUGAUUUUGAAUACAUUUGUAGCCUCAUACACUCUUACUACAGCCCUGUGAGGAAGUUCUAAGAUUGAGAGAUGUGUCUAAUACCAUAUAGCUGGUAGAAGGUCACUGAAGCUUAAAUACAGGUUUUCCAAUUCAGAGUUCUUUCUCAAGGUGAUUUAGAGAGCAUAUCAGAAUUAUGUUUUACCAUGCUGCUAUAUUUUUGUAGCAUUUAGCUGAGAAAUAAAAUUUAUACCAAUCUCAGUUCUAGUAACUAUGUGUUUUAAAGUCUAAAUUAAAAUACACAAAAAGCAUAGUUACCUAUAAGUCUGUCUCUAAGAUAACGUCAAAGAAGAAGGGGCAGAAAGAGUAGUUUUGUGCUUUUUAUUGUGUUAAUUUCACAAGUUUCUUUUUCUUUUCUUUUUUGAGAUGAAAUCUUGCUGUCGCCCAGGCUGGAGUGCAGUGGCACUAUCUUGGCUCACUGCAACUUUGCCUCCCAGGUUCAAGCGAUUCUCCUGCCUCAGCCUCCCUAGUAGCUGGGAUUACAGAUUUCCAACUGAUACCAUACAGCGCUCAAAAUGGAUCAGGGCUGUUAAUCGUGUGGACCCCAGAAGCAAAAAGAUUUGGAUUCCAGGACCAGGUGCUAUACUGUGUUCCAAACAUUUUCAAGAAAGUGACUUUGAGUCAUAUGGCAUAAGAAGAAAGCUGAAAAAAGGAGCUGUGCCUUCUGUUUCUCUAUACAAGAUUCCUCAAGGUGUACAUCUUAAAGGUAAAGCAAGACAAAAAAUCCUAAAACAACCUCUUCCAGACAAUUCUCAAGAAGUUGCUACUGAGGACCAUAACUAUAGUUUAAAGACACCUUUGACGAUAGGUGCAGAGAAACUGGCUGAGGUGCAACAAAUGUUACAAGUGUCCAAAAAAAGACUUAUCUCCGUAAAGAACUACAGGAUGAUCAAGAAGAGAAAGGGUUUACGAUUAAUUGAUGCACUUGUAGAAGAGAAACUACUUUCUGAAGAAACAGAGUGUCUGCUACGAGCUCAAUUUUCAGAUUUUAAGUGGGAGUUAUAUAAUUGGAGAGAAACAGAUGAGUACUCCGCAGAAAUGAAACAAUUUGCAUGUACACUCUACUUGUGCAGUAGCAAAGUCUAUGAUUAUGUAAGAAAGAUUCUUAAGCUGCCUCAUUCUUCCAUCCUCAGAACGUGGUUAUCCAAAUGCCAACCCAGUCCAGGUUUCAACAGCAACAUUUUUUCUUUUCUUCAACGAAGAGUAGAGAAUGGAGAUCAGCUCUAUCAAUACUGUUCAUUGUUAAUAAAAAGUAUGCCUCUCAAGCAACAGCUUCAGUGGGAUCCUAGCAGUCACAGUUUGCAGGGGUUUAUGGACUUUGGUCUUGGAAAACUUGAUGCUGAUGAAACGCCACUUGCUUCAGAAACUGUUUUGUUAAUGGCAGUGGGUAUUUUUGGCCAUUGGAGAACACCUCUUGGUUAUUUUUUUGUAAACAGAGCAUCUGGAUAUUUGCAGGCUCAGCUGCUUCGUCUGACUAUUGGUAAACUGAGUGACAUAGGAAUCACAGUUCUGGCUGUUACAUCUGAUGCCACAGCACAUAGUGUUCAGAUGGCAAAAGCAUUGGGGAUACAUAUUGAUGGAGACGACAUGAAAUGUACAUUUCAGCAUCCUUCAUCUUCUAGUCAACAGAUUGCAUACUUCUUUGACUCUUGCCACUUGCUAAGAUUAAUAAGAAAUGCAUUUCAGAAUUUUCAAAGCAUUCAGUUUAUUAAUGGUAUAGCACAUUGGCAGCACCUCGUGGAGUUAGUAGCACUGGAGGAACAGGAAUUAUCAAAUAUGGAAAGAAUACCAAGUACACUUGCAAAUUUGAAAAAUCAUGUACUGAAAGUGAAUAGUGCCACCCAACUCUUUAGUGAGAGUGUAGCCAGUGCAUUAGAAUAUUUGUUAUCCUUAGACCUGCCACCUUUUCAAAACUGUAUUGGUACCAUCCAUUUUUUACGUUUAAUUAACAAUCUGUUUGACAUCUUUAAUAGUAGGAACUGUUAUGGAAAGGGACUUAAAGGGCCUCUGUUGCCUGAAACUUACAGUAAAAUAAACCACGUGUUAAUUGAAGCCAAGACUAUUUUUGUUACAUUAUCUGACACUAGCAAUAAUCAAAUAAUUAAAGGUAAGCAAAAACUAGGAUUCCUGGGAUUUUUGCUCAAUGCUGAGAGCUUAAAAUGGCUCUACCAAAAUUAUGUUUUCCCAAAGGUCAUGCCUUUUCCUUAUCUUCUGACUUACAAAUUCAGUCAUGAUCAUCUGGAAUUAUUUCUAAAGAUGCUUAGGCAGGUAUUAGUAACAAGUUCUAGCCCUACCUGCAUGGCAUUCCAGAAAGCUUACUAUAAUUUGGAGACCAGAUACAAAUUUCAAGAUGAAGUUUUUCUAAGCAAAGUAAGCAUCUUUGACAUUUCAAUUGCUCGAAGGAAAGACUUGGCGCUUUGGACAGUUCAACGUCAGUAUGGUGUCAGCGUUACAAAGACUGUCUUUCACGAAGAGGGUAUUUGUCAAGACUGGUCUCAUUGUUCACUAAGUGAGGCAUUACUAGACCUGUCAGAUCAUAGGCGAAAUCUCAUCUGUUAUGCUGGUUAUGUUGCAAACAAGUUAUCAGCUCUUUUAACUUGUGAGGACUGCAUCACUGCACUGUAUGCAUCGGAUCUCAAAGCCUCUAAAAUUGGGUCACUAUUAUUUGUUAAAAAGAAGAAUGGUUUGCAUUUUCCUUCAGAAAGUCUGUGUCGGGUCAUAAAUAUUUGUGAGCGAGUUGUAAGAACCCAUUCAAGAAUGGCAAUUUUUGAACUAGUUUCUAAACAAAGGGAAUUGUAUCUUCAACAGAAAAUAUUAUGUGAGCUUUCUGGGCAUAUUAAUCUUUUUGUAGAUGUGAAUAAGCAUCUCUUUGAUGGAGAAGUGUGUGCCAUCAAUCACUUUGUCAAGUUGCUAAAGGAUAUAAUAAUCUGUUUCUUAAAUAUCAGAGCUAAAAAUGUUGCACAGAAUCCUUUAAAACAUCAUUCAGAGAGAACUGAUAUGAAAACUUUAUCAAGGAAACACUGGUCAUCUGUACAGGAUUAUAAAUGUUCAAGUUUUGCUAAUACCAGUAGUAAAUUCAGGCAUUUGCUAAGUAACGAUGGAUAUCCAUUCAAAUGAGAGACCUAAAAUAUAUUAACAUUUUAAUUAAGAAUACUUGAUCAACAUUUUUUGAAGUUCAAUUUACCAUAUUUUAUAAAUUGCGCAUUCUGCACAGUGGACAAGUUUGCAAUUCUGACUUAUUAAAAUUUCAAAUUCUGCAUAUCACAAAAUCUCCUUAUACUUUUGGUAUGGCUUGCAGCAUUUAUGAGUUUUCCAAAAUAUAGAAAGCAGUAGGUCAGUAGGAGCAAACUAGCCAACAGGUACUGUCUUUGAAUUUACUACUGUAAGACUAAGCAGUGUUACUGGACACAGUUUUAACUUGUUCAAUCUGCUUCAAAAACAAGAAAAACAACAACUAUGAGUUAUCAAAAUAUUGACUCCAUUUAUGACUAGACUACAUUUCUGAAAGAUCUUUGGUUUAUGAUUCUUAAGAAUAUUGACAAUACCUAUAAAACUUUGAAGAUAACUUUUACUUAAAUAUGAAAAUUAUAGUUUGAAAAUUAGGCUCAAGCAAAUAUCAAAUACUGCAAAAAUCCCCUUGUCCCAGGAUACCCUAAAAUAGAAGUGCUUAAACUUUGUCAGGCAGAAGGUAAAGUACAUGAGCCAUGAGAUUCUUCCUUGUGCUGCAGCCACGCUGGGGAGUGCAAUCUGGAAAGAACAUACCUAAUGUGUUUUUCACCAUCCAUUAUCUCUGAACUUUGAAAUAUUACUUUUGAAUAAUAGGCUGGACACUUAGUUUGACUUGAAAGAGCUCAAUGCUCAUCGGAAAACAGGGAGAAACCUAAUCUGAAGAUGGAAGCAUACUAAGGACAAUUUUCUCCACUCACAUCCACAUUUGAAAAGAGGGACAGAAAAACAUAGGUAACUCUACUUUCACAAAUGAGGAUAGUUUAACGGAUAGAAGAAACAAGCACAUUAUUCACCUGUGUUGUAAAACAUCUACUCUUUUUUGUCACUGAAUAAGUGUUCCCAAAGUACAGUUAAUCCUAAUAUGAAAACUUAGAAUUGUAAAAGAUUAAUGAUAACGUAAAAGUAUAUUGAUUAAAAUUCCCCUUACAAAGUA